GUUCUUCUGCUGCCACCGCUGUCGGCACCAUGGGCAGUGAGCAGAGCUCCGAGGCCGAGAGCCGACCCAACGAUCUGAACUCCUCAGGUCGGUGUCCUAACCUCCCACCCUCCUCCAGCCCGCCCUGUCCCCUUGCAGAGCGGGCUGCCUCCCAGACUAGGGUCAGGGACUGCGGACGGGAACGCACAGAAAAAGCCUUCACCGUGCUAGUAGGAAAAAAAAAAAGUCACCAUCUGUCCUGGCCUCGAUUCCCCUGAUGGAAGUGCGUGUGACUGCAAGCUAAGCCAGCGUGGGCGCCAGUGCCCUUAUUUAUUUUCAAAACAGCCGUUUCUCCCAGCUACAGCCUCCUGUUUAAAAGACGAGCUAAUUAAUUUUUGGCUCUAGUGCUCAUGGCUGAUGUAGUGAGAUUUGGCUCACACAGUGGAUGGAUUAUAGGACCUCUAAGAACAGUCUGUUUCUUAAAAACGGGUGUUAGAGGUUCCUUUUCUGAAGGGAUAUGUGAUAGGUGUCCACUUGCUUUGAACCCUUUAGUGCAAAGGUCUCCAGAAACAGCUUUUUCUUCUCAGAAGGUGUCUUGGUCCGUUUUCUAAUCUUGUAGAGGUUGGCCAGACAGCAGGCACUGGUGUUUUCCAUUGUUGUUCUCUGUCCAUGAUUUUUAGACUUCUCUAAGCGUUUGAGACAAGAAUGGGAGGAUUAUUGUGUUUGCAAUACAGUGAGUGUUCAAUAAAUAGAUAAAGCAGCUGAUGUUUAAUUGAGGACCAUUUGCUGCUUUUUUUGUUACCCACACGCUAGGACAGCUGGGAGUGCUUUGGUUAAGCUCCGGGGUUGCUAACGCAAAUUGGUUAAAUCUGGGGCCUAAAAAGAGUCGCCGAUUUUAGAAGUUCUCUGUUCUUGAUAGGAGCUGUAAUUCAGAAAUAGGCAAGCUAAUAGAUCUAAGGGUGUUUCACUUUAAGGUGUGACUUUCAAGACUAGUUCAGACCUACAUUCUGGGGACUGGAUUGGGGCAGCUUUGAAUGUGACUCCUUCACCAGCCAAGCAUAGAGCCAAGAUGGAUGAUAUUGUGGUUGUAGCUCAGGGCUCCCAGGCCUCACGGAACGUCAGCAACGAUCCCGAUGUCAUCAAGUUGCAAGAGAUUCCAACCUUCCAGCCCCUUUUGAAAGGGCUAUUGAGUGGCCAGACUUCCCCAACAAAUGCCAAAUUGGAGAAACUGGACUCUCAGCAGGUGUUGCAGCUCUGCCUCCGAUAUCAAGAUCACCUGCAUCAGUGUGCAGAGGCCGUUGCUUUUGACCAGAAUGCUUUGGUUAAACGAAUCAAAGAGAUGGAUCUGUCUGUAGAAACUCUGUUCAGCUUCAUGCAGGAGCGCCAGAAAAGAUACGCCAAGUAUGCCGAGCAGAUCCAGAAAGUGAACGAGAUGUCCGCCAUCCUCCGCCGCAUACAGAUGGGCAUCGACCAGACUGUGCCCCUGCUGGACAGGCUCAACAGCAUGCUGCCCGAGGGCGAGCGGCUGGAGCCCUUCAGCAUGAAGCCCGACCGCGAGCUCAGGCUGUAGCUGCUGCCCGGCCUGCCUGGGGCUGGGAGCCCCAGACACCGACACCCUGAGGACGUGUGGAGCUAAGGUCAUAUCAUCUGACCAGGUCUGGAGGCUGGCGGGAGGCUCCCUGAAAGUGGGUGCGAAGGAGUCCGGCUGGCAUGAAAAUCUGACUUUGCCCAGCUCUUUUCCUUGAUGCAGUUUCCCGGUGUGGAAGGAACCUAACCAGUUCUCGGUGAUAACUGAAGCUGGAACGUGUGAAUUAUUAGGAAUUCUUUGAAGAACUCUGCAUUGAGAAUUAUUUUUAUUUAGUUUUUUUUUUUUUUUAAUUGAGAGUAUAUAGUCCAGUCCAGGUACCGGAAUAAAAAUAUGGAGACAAGGGGAAAAUAUUUUACGAAGCUCUGUGUUCUCAACGCCCUCAUGAACUUUUCAGUAGGCUGUCUGGUUUAUGUGUGGUCAACUUGAAAAACUAAUUGAAUCUAGGUCUCUGUAUUGUUCCUGUUUCUACCCUGACUGUUUCCGUCACACCAAGCCCUUAUCUGGGGCGCGUCUUCCUGCCCAGGUGGAACACUGGCAUUUUGUUGACUGUCAGGUUAGGUGUCCCUUAGUCGUCAUCAGAAGCUGAAGCCUUCCUUUCCACACCCUCAUCAGAUUCAUCUCCACUGAUAACCGGUUUCCUUGAUGCAGACAUAGUUUAGCUUUCUUUGACUGCAGAGAUGUCUCAUUCCACAGACAUUUCUUGAACCCAUUUGAUGUGUCCAAUAUUGUGCCAGGGAUACAAAUAUGGCCGUAUAGCCUCAGGCCUUCAUUUCUGAAAAGAAAAAAGCUCAAAAAGCUGCUGAAUUUCUCUGGGAGUUUAGGAAAGGAAGUUAUUUGAGUAACAACAAAAGUGCUUAGUGUCGUACUUUACACAUCAUAGGUGUUCUAAUGGAAGCAAGGACUGGAGAAGCAAAGAGUGGAAUGUGAGGAGCAGACCUAGGCAGACACCUUGAGACUAAAAGUCAGAGCUGAAGGGAGUCGCUGGGGCCAGGACGGCAUGCAGGCCUGUACCCUGUUCCCUAAGUUCCUGCAAGCGUCGGGAGGUGUGUUUUCAGAUACCAGAAAGAGCCUUCAGUAGAUUCACAAGAUUAAAAUUGAUGCGCUUAAUUUAAUGUAUCUUGGCUAAACUUGAUCUGAUUCUAAUCUUGGUUUGAGACAGGGUCUUGUGCUGUUGCUCAGGCUGGAGUGCAGUGGCGCAAUCAUAGCACACUGACUCCUCAAACUCCCGGGCUCCGGGGAUCCUCACGCCUCAGACUCCUGAGUAGCUGGGAUUACAGGUGUGUGCCACCAAAUCCAGCUAAUUAAAAAAAAUUAAUUAAUUUUACAUUUUCAAAUUCAAAAGAAUAAUACAAUGAAUAUUCAUAUUUCUUUCACCUAGAUUGACAAAAAGUGGUAUAUUUAAGACAUCACCAUCAUUGUCUUUCUUCUGGAGUAUACAGAACCUGGUUCUGAACACAGGGAUAUGUUUGUAGCUUCGAGGAAUGAAGGGCUGUUUACAGAGCUACAAAAAUAGCUUAGGUGCCAUUAUCCUCACUGCACUUAAUACAGGUGACACAUGAAAGCACAGAGUGGGUGGCAGUUCAAGCCUGCGAGGGCCGAGCCUUUCCACUGCUGCAGCUGUUAGUGGCUGGCACAGGGCAGGAUGGCAGACCUAGUGCAGCACAAACAAACCACGCAGUCAGCCAGCUCUCCAGCCAACUGUGUCUACUUCUAAAGUAGAAGUUAGACAAAACAUGGGGUUCACUUAGACUGGGGUCCUGAGUAGGUGAUAGGCUACUUAUUACUGGGUGGAAGCGGAGAAGUAUGGCAGAAGAACAAUAGGCAAAUUCAAUACUCCCGGAAAGAAUUCUAGUUAGUUUAAUAUUUUGAUGGCAUGUUGUGGUUUCUGCAGUGUCGUGAACUUGGCUAAACUGAACUGUGUUCCCAGAAUUCCCUUCCUUGUUUGUUUCUCUGGUGAGGGUUGGCCACGAGAGAGAUUUGCAUGAGGUUUGGAAGUGGAAGUAGAGCAACAGCCAUGUGUAUUCACUGGAAGUGGAUGUAGGUCAGGCCCUGUUCCAUCACGUGCACGUUACCAUGGAUCUCCUGCACUUGUGGUGUGGGCAGCCGCUGGGCCCACGGCUCCUCCCACUCCCGCAGAACUCUGCCUUUGGCUUUUCCAGACCCUGGGCCGGGUAUGAGAACCAGCUUCUUGGUCUGCAGCCACAAGGAUGAAGGUUUGGGGAUGAGAGACCAGCACGGGCUCUGAUGAGAGACAGGUGCAGGUCCCAGCUUGUGGCUUGCAGGUCUCAGUCGUACUUGCUCUCCCUCACCAUCCUUUCCAACCGCCUGGCCUGUGGUCUGGUGAAGAAGAAACAGCCGAACCGAGACUUUCACCAGCCCCUCUAAUUGCUCAAACCGCUUUCACAAUCCUCUCUUUCUACAUCAUUCCUAGUGGUUCUUUUCUGAUGGAACCUCUGACUGGUAACAUGGCAUUACCAGUCCUUUCCCUCUCAUGUUUUGCUAUUUCCUGAUGGAACCUGGGAGUCUGAGUGAUUUGUAUUUCAAGAAGCAGUUAUGCUGGAUCUCUUUGUUGGUUAAUACCCCAUGACCUAUCUGGCCGUUAUGGGAUAUUUCAGGGAUAGGAGUUGUGAAAGAGCCCUUGGCUGGACGUUUCUAGCCUUAAUCUUUGGCAAGCCAUUUCAUUUCCCUGAGCCUCAGUUUCCGCCUUCCUACAGCGUGAGCAGGUCUGGGUGGGCUCUCAAGCCCCUUUCAGCUCUAAGAUUCCAAGUCUGUGAUUCCGAUACAUCUUGACUACAAUGAGCGUGUUUACCUUUUGUCUCUGAGCAGUGGCCCUGGGUCUUGGUAGUGACUAAAUUCCGAGCUCCCAAGGUGCAGCUGCUUUUCUUCCUUUUAAUUAUAAAUUAGCUGUUCAUUGGCUGCUUCUUUCUAGAGCCUGUUUUGCUUAUCUUGCAAUCUGUUCAUUUCUGUUGAUGAACACAGUCAAAUAGGCCUCUAUGUGCAGUCUCCUGGUUUCCCUGGUCAAAGUGGAAGGUUGGUAGAAACUGGCCUUCAUGUCUUUGUUUCCCUCAAAGUUUUAUUCUUAGUAACGCUAUAUAUGGUUUUAUAGACCACACAUAUAUAGUUUCCUGUGUCUUAGAUGAUAACAUCCUUAAAAUAUGAAAUAUAUUUUGAACCUAGAUACCUACCCAGUAUUCUCUGCACAGAGUAAACAUUUCAUUAAAUGAGUUUCAAGGACUCCAUACCCUGAUAUAGGAGUACAUUCAAGAAAUGAGUUUAGGCCGGGCGCGGUGGCUCACACCUGUAAUCCCAGCACUUUGGGAGGCCGAGACGAGUGGAUCACCUGAGGUCAGGAGUUCCAGACCAGCCUGACCAACAUGGUGAAACCCCAUCUCUACUAAAAAAAAUACAGAAAUUACCCGGGCAUGGUGGCUGGUGCCUGUAAUCCCCGCUACUUGGGAGGCCAAGGUGGGAGAAUCGCUUGAACCUGGGAGGCGGAGGUUGCAGUGAGCCAAGUUCGUGCCAUUGCACUCUGGCCUGGGUAACAAGAGUGAAACUCCGUUUAGAAAUGAGUUUAGUCUGGGAGAAUCUGCUUUUUGAGUAAAAAAGUUUGAUUUUAUGUAUGUGUGCGUCUGUAUAUAUGUUUCUGUAUCCUGAGUAUUUCUUUGCGGCUUCUUCAGUUAUGAAAGAGGUUGGUACUGUUACCCUUACGUUAUAGGUAUUACAAACUCGGUUUUACAAGGUUACAUAAACUAAUGGCCCUGGGGCGAAUGACGUAUGCCACUUUUGUGUUGAUUUGUAGAACUUACUUAGCUUUGGCAUUUCCCCUAGUAAUUCCCAAGGCAAAACCAGGAAUUGUCAGAGACGUGACCAGACAUGUAUUAAAAUUCUAGUGCAAUUGGGAAACUUGGUCUUCCUGAUUUGUUUAUACUUCAGCCAAACCCAGAUAUAUAGUGCUCAGCAGAAAUUAUUCAAAAUGUUGAUACUCAAGAUUGAAGGAUGGAUUAGGGAGAAAUGAAAACUUUUCUUCUUGUGGACUUUUUAGGUAUGAAAUUUAAUCACGAGAGUAGUUUUGCUUUUCUUUCCCUGACCUUUCGCUUCAUUCCUUUGUUAAGAACUAUAUAGUGCCUCUGAGGAGGUGGCAUUAUUGUUCACUAACUUACCAUAAAUCAGGGGUCUCCAAACCCCAGGCCACAGACUGGUACCCAUCUGUGGCGUGUGAGGAAGUGUGCUGCACAGCAGGAGGUGAGCGGCGGAUGAGCAGGUGAAGCUUCACGUGUUGUUGUUGUUGUUUAUUGAGAUGGAGUCUCGCUCUGUUGCCCAGGCUGGAGUGCAGUGGCACGAUCUCGGCUCACUGCAACCUCCGCCUCCCGGGUUCAAGCAGUUAUACUGUCUCAGCCUCCCGAGUAGCUGGGACUACAGGUGCCCGCCACCACACCCGGCUAAUUUUUUAUUUUUAGUAGAGAUGGGGUUUCACCAUGUUGGCCAGGCAGGUCUCAAACUCCUGACCUCGUGAUCUGCCCGACUUGGCCUCCCAAAGUACUGGGAUUACAGGCGUGAGCCACUGCACCUGGCCAGCUUCGUGUGUAUUUAUAGCUGCUCCCCAUCACUCACAUCACUGCCUGAGCUCCACCUCCUGUCAGAACAGACCCAGCAUUAGACUCCCCUAAGAGCGUGAACCCUAUUGUGAACUGCGCACGUGAAGGAUCUAGGUUUUGCGCUCCUUAUGAGAAUCUAAUGCCUGAUGAUCUGAGAUGGAACGGUUUCAUCCAGAAACCAUCCCCCUGCUUCCCUGUCUGUAGAAAAAUUGUCUUCUAUGAAAUGGGUCCCUGGUGCCAGAAAGGUUGGGGACUGCUGUCAUAAAUAACAUUGAAUUUCAUGUGGGUUUUUUUUUUUUGACACACCAGGCAUGUCUCUUCCAUUCAAAUGCUAUGGCUACAGAGGGAAAGGGUAGCCAGAUAAUUAUCCACAUGCUUCAAACCAAAAAGAUAAAAAAGUUGGCAACUAGAUCUAGUUGCCUGCCAGGAUGACCAGCGUUAUGCUGGUGUGUGCGUGUCCAUGCCUCCGGGAUUUUUCCAGGGUUAUCAAUGUCAGUGUAAGAUCUGAUGGAAUUUACCGUUGACUCAAUUUUCUUCACCAAUCAAGGCUCAUUCCUUGAGGCAUGAGUUAUGCGAAAAGCUUUUCUGCACCAAGUACUUUCAUUCUGGUCUUUGGAAUUGUCAUAAUUCUGACAGAGAACACAGACCAUUACUGAAUGCUCUUCAGGUUACCCUAUUUGCCUGUCACAUUGCUUCUACCGGCCACAUCCUGCAUUUCCUGUGGGACAGCAUUUUCAAACGGAUUCUAGUGUUUGAGCUGGAACCAAAAGAAUGAAACUGUUUUUACAUAAGUGCAUAUUGCUGUCUCUGCAAAUAAAGUACAACAAUAUGACUGACUUGUAAA